AUGAUAGAUGCAAAAGAUGACAAACUGCUGGUUUACCAAAACCAGCCUGCAGAUGCAAAGACAGGCUCUCCAGGAAGACUUCCUGGAGGAGGCGGGCCUCAGCUGGACCGCAGGCGGCCAGGAGGAGCUGGGGGUGGUGGUGGUGGGGGCGAGGGUGAAGGUGGUUGGAGAUCGGGGGAGAGUGUGAAGAGGAGGACGAGGCCCGGACCUGGGCCUUUCCAGGCAGGCGGCCCAAACGGAUCUACGCAGCCAGCCACCCCUCCCAGCUGGGGUCGGCGCGUCCCCCUCCAGGCCGGUGUGGGGAGAGUCUGGCCGUCUGGAGGCCCGGGGCAGCAGGACUGGGAGAGCCGCGGUCUCCUUCCUGUCCCCUGCUCCCGGCAGACCCGCGUUUCCAGGGCCCUGUCCUUUACCCGGGGCGGCCGUCCUCCCAUGCCCAGCCUCUGCGAGGCCACCGCUCCCCGCAGCGCCGGUGUCACGGCCCCACGGAGGGCCAGGAGCCUCCAGGGCGCCCCAGCGGCGGGGUGGACGCUGCCAGGCGGUACCACGGCAGGGCCCGCGCCGCCCAUCCCGCGCCACGCCCCCACCUCCGCCGGCACCGUUGCCAGCAGCCCGGCUGCGAGCCCGCCGGCGCCCGGCCACCCGCCCGCUGCGUCGCCUGGCAGCGCGCCUGCAGCUGAGUCAGCCUGUUGCAACCUGCUGUAUGAAGAACACCUUUGAAGGUAUCAGACGUAUCUGUCUUUUCUCUUAAAUACAAUGCACAGCAGCAGGAAAGGGCCUGCUCACCUGCUGGCCAGAGGCUUCCUGGCUCUCAGCCUCCUUGACUACUUUUUUUGAGACAGGGUCUUGCAGUGUCACCCAGGCUGGAGUGCAGUGGCGCGAACACGGCUCACUGCCGCCUCAACGUCCCAGGUGCAAGUGAUCAUCCUGCCUCAGCCUCCCAAGUAGCUGGGACUACCGGCAUGGACCGCCACACCUGGCUAAUUUUUUAAUUUUUUGUAGAGAUGGGGUCUCACUAUGUUGUUCAAGCUGGUCUCAAAAAACUCCUGGGCUCAAGCGAUCCUCCUGCCUCAGCCUCCCAAAGUGCUGGGAUCCACAACUCCCAAUGAUUCCCAGGGACCUGAGACAGAGCCUCCAUGGGCAAUAAACACACCAUGGUUUGUGUUUGUUUGUGUUUGGAUGUGCAUUGAAUCCUGGUAACUGUGAUUACCUGGGGUGGGAGGGCACUGGGGAUGAGGGAGGACUUUUCACUGUACUUUGCUGCUGUUUGAAUUUUUGUCACGUAUAUAUUACUUAAAAAUGUUUAUUUAAAAGCAUUUCAGACCUACAAAAAGGUGUCAGAAACAAAUGUGACACACAGUCACGCUGCCUUUCUCCCCAUUCCACACCCUGCAGAAAUCUCUAGCUAGCUUCAGUACUUCUCUGAGGAGUGAGGAGUGGAUGAAGCCUCAGAAUGCUUUAUUUUAUAUAUAAUUUUUUUUCCUUUUUUUUUUUUUUUGAGAUGAAGUCACACAGUAUUGCCCAGGCUGGUCUCAAAUUCCUGGGCUCAAGCAAUCCUCCUGCCUUGCUCAAGCAUGAGCCAGUAUGCCUGGCCAAGGAGCUGAUUUCUGAUCUAGGUCUUGAAAUUUUUUUUCUUUUUCUUUUCUUUUCUUUCUUUUUUUUUUUUUUUUGGUAAACUUUUGUUUUAGGUUCACGGUGUAUGUGCAGGUUUGUUAUAUAGGUAAACUUGUAUCAUGGGGGUUUGUGGUACAGAUUAUUUCAUCACCCAGGUACUAUGCCUAGUACCCAAUUCAAAUUCUUUUCUUUCUUCUUCUUCUUCUUUUUUUUUUUUUUGAGGAAGGGUCUCACUCUGUGGGCUGGCGUGCAGUGGCGCGAUCUCAGCUCACUGCAACCUCUGAAUCCCAGGCUCAGGUGAUCCUCCCACCUCAGCCUCCUAAGUGGCACACACCACCAUACCCAGCUAAUUUUUCUAUUUUUAAUAGAGAUGGGGUUUCUCCAUGUUGCCCAGGCUGGUCUCGAACUCCUAGGCUCAAGCAAUCCACCUGCUUUGGCCUCCCAAAGUGCUGGGAUUACAGGCAUGAGCCACCUUGCCCGGCCCCAAUUCGGAAUUCUUAACACAGUCUUCUGAGUAGUGUCACCAGUUGAUCAUAUCAGAAUUUUUGAAAGCCGUUGGCUGUCCUGUAGACUGUCCCCUCCGACAUUGUCCACAGCACCAAAUCUGGCCUGCAGAUGGUGUGGGGCCAUCUCAUCAGCAGGCAGGUCUGUCCCAGGUCCUGAUUCUGCCCAGGGAACUGGCAGUUCCUGAGAAGUGAGAGGUAUGCAGUUACCUCUCAACACCUCUUCAGUCCGUAUCCCCCAGAGCAUUUAAGGUCUUUCUGGGGAAAUAUAACAAAAACCAAGAGUAAUUAAGAUGGGACUUGGACUCUGGCCUGGAGAAGAUUCUAAUGUAGCUGGAGAACAAUACAAAGCAGCAAAAAUAAGAUUGCUUAUGUGUUGGGUGUACGUGUUUAAUUAUGUAGGCCUUUGGGCAUUAUUUGGUCUCAGAAUCCUGGGGCUUGGAAGGCCCUGGAGGAGCCUCCUCUAGGACAUGGGACCUGAAAAAUCUCCUAGCUGGUGGUUGCCACUGUGAAUCCCUCUCUCCAGGACAGAGAAACCUGACAUUAUCUGGGCCCCCACAUUUGAUCUGGCUUGUUCUAAAUCAACUCUUGAGAGCCUGCCGUAUAAAGAAGAAAGUGCCCUUUGGCUCACUGGGAGUAAGAAAUACAGCCGUCAGGAGAAACAGAAAGUCCGUGCCUGCUGCAGGCAUCCUCCUGGUCCACAGGAAACUCCACCAGGAAAGGCAAUUAUUACAGAAGAGAACACUGCUUGGAGUUGUGGACACUGUUGCCUACCCAGCUUCCAUUCUCCCCUUCCUUCCUAAUAGCACCCCAGUUUUAGCACCCCAGUUUUGUUCAGGUAUCUGCCUGUCUACACAUGCUUCAGGGAAAGCUGACCCAUGCUCAGCCCCUUGCCUGCAGCUCCUGAGUGGGGGUUGGGAAGCUGAUUUUUCAGAGAGUGAUCCCAUUGCAUUUGCCAACUUGUGCAUGGCAUUUCCUGGCCCAAGGUUUACUUCAGGAAUGGGUUUGUAAUCAAAUUCAGCCCAGUGAAAUAUGAGGAUAAGUUUGGAGACUUCUGGGGAAGAAACGUGCUCCUGUUCUUUAAGGAAAGAACUACCAGAAGAGCCCUCAUUCUCCUCCAGAGUGGCAAGCAGAUAUGGGAACUGAAACUUCAAGAACCAUUUGGCUAUCAGGAAGGAGGCAGCCUGACAACAAAGACAGCCCCAGAAGAGGAUGUGAUUAAGGAAAUCAGAGAGAAACAGAGCCAGGUUGCUGGAUCAUUCUGAUCCUGAAGCCUCCAUUACAUCUAAUCACAGACUGCUGUGGUUGGCAGAGGGGUGCAUCUUUGAUUGCCGCUGGGGACGAAAGCAGAGUCCCGAAAGCAGAUGUCCCAGCUGGGUCCCGCACCUCUCCCUGCCAUUGCCCCCUGGGUCCCACUGAUGUCCUGUUUCCAGUCCAGGAUCCCAUUCAGAAUCCAACAUGGCACUUGUCUCCUCCCAUGUGGGGCAGUUCCCCCGUCUUUCCUUGUCGCUGUGACACUGGCCAGCUAUUUUAUAGGACAUUUCUCACUUUGGAUUUGUCUGAUGUUUUCUCAGUAUUAGAUUGAGGAUAUGCAUUUUUGGCACAAAUGCCAAAGAAGUGAUGCUGUGCGCCUCUCAGGACACUGUCAAGGGCGGGGUGAUAAUAUGUCUCAUUACUGGUCAUGGUAGCUUGGAUCACUUGGUUAAAGUGGUGUCUCUGAAGUUUCUCCACUGGAAAGUUGCUAUUUUCCCUUUGUAAUUAAUAAAUGUCCUGUGGGGGAGAUGCUUUAUGAGUAUGUAAAUAUCCUGUUUCUCAUCAUAUUUUUGCCUACUCAUUUUAGCAUCGGUUGAUGAUUCCUGGCUGCAACAGUUAUUACCAUAGUUUUUAGCAAAUGGUGAUUUUCUUUGUAUAUCACUCUUUCUGUAUUUAUUGAUUGGAAUUCUACUGUAAAAAAGAACUCUUUCCUCCA